UUUUUUUUUUUUUUUGAGAUGGAGUCUCACUCUGUCGCCCAGGGCUGGAGUGCAGUGGCAUGAUCUCGGCUCACUGCAAGCUCUGCCUCCCGGGUUCAUGCCAUUUUCCUGCCUCAGCCUCCCAAGUAGCUGGGACUACAGAUGCCCACCACCUCGCCCGGCUAAUUUUUUUGUAUGUUUAGUAGAGACGGGGUUUCACCGUGUUAGCCAGGAUGGUCUCGAUCUCCUAACCUCGUGAUCCACCCAAAUUUGAUUACUGCCAUCCUAAAUGCCAUUGGGUUAUCUGAAUAUGUGAUGCAUUCGUAUCUCCCAGUACUAUCAAGGAUAAAGGAGGUAAUAAAUUCAGAUAUUGGCAGGACUUUGUGUAGUAGGGAAAGUAUGGAAAAGGUUGCUGCCUACCUUAGUUACAAUAGGUUGAAUUCAUCAAAGGACUUCCAACUGGAAAAGGAGAAACUUGAAAUAGAGAUUACAAGUCAUGCAAUAACUAUGAUUCUUAGGUGCAUAUGUUUAUGGAUAUAUUAGUUUCCUAGGGCCGCUGUAUUUUAAGCCACUAAUUUUGUGGCUUAAAAUAACAGGUGUUUCUUAUUACACAGUUCUGGAGGCUAGAAGUUCAAAAUUAAGGUGUCAAGAUCAUACUUCCUGUGAAGGUUCUAGGGAAUCCUUCUUUGCCUCUUCCUAGCUUCUGGUGGUUGCCUGCAGUUCCUUGACUUUCCUUGUAAGACAUACACACAUCACUCCAAACUCUGCCUCUAUCUUUACAUGGCAUUCUUUGUGUGUCUCUUCUUGUAAGGAAAUCACUGAUUUGAUUUAGGGCUCAUCCUCAUCCAGUGUGUCCUCAUCUUAACUAAUCACAUUUGCCAAGUAUUUCCAAAUAAUGUUACAUUCUGAGGUUCUGGGUAGACAUGAGCUUUGAGGAGACACUAUUCAACCCAGUUUAGUGGGUGUGGGCAUUUGUGUAUAGUUUUAUGGGUGGAGGGGGACACCUAGGAAACUAUCAUAAUCUCUGUGAGAAUGCACAUUCUAAUUUUCUUCAGAGUUUAUUUCUACUUUUACUUAAGUAGUUUAAUUUGAGAAUGGUGUGAAUGUGGGGGAAAUGUUAGAAACCACUGACUUAAAACAAUAGUUUUAAAUUGUAUGUUGAAUAAGUCCCUAUUUGCUGCUAUUCCUUGAACUUAGUUUCCUUGGCUCCAUAGUGUAUUUUGAAGCAAAGGGCAGGACAUAUGCACCAUGAAGUGGUAAUAUGAAAAGAUGGAGGCCAUUAGUUUAGCAUGUGCUGGUAUUCGUCUAUUUUUCCAUAAAGUAUAGCUCUUCAGUUAAUCAUUGUCCUGGUAUACAAGGGAAAUUUUUAAUUAUGACCUUCUUACUAUGAGUAAUUCCUGGCUUUUGAGGAUAUCUUAAGGAUAUGGAUCUUUCACACUCCUAUGCUGAAGAUCUUUGAAUUUUCUUUUCCUGUGCUUGACAUCGAGUGCUGAAUGUAGUUUAGUACAUGUCUUAGAUUCCAAAUGUCUAAAAGCAUUUUUAUCACAUAUCAUUAAGUAGCAGCAUUUUCCAAAGCAGUCAUCUAUCAUGUUGUAAUCUUUCUGAUUGGAUGGUAAAUGCAUCCUUACAAAUUAUCAGCAUUACAGUAUUUCAUCAAAAUGGAAUAUGCACUUUGGGAGGCUGAGACGGAAGGAUCGCUUGAGCCCAGGAGUUCCAAACCAUCCAAGAAAUUUGACGAGACUCUGUCUGUAUGGAACAUAAAAAAUUAGCCAGGCAUGGUGGCAUGCACCUGUAGUCCCAGCUACUCAGAGGCCUGAGGCAGGAGCAUCACUUGAGCCAAGAAGGUUGACACUGCUGUGAGCUGUGUUCAUACCAGAUGCACUCCAGCCUGGGAGACAGAAUGAGAUUCUCUCUGAAAAACAAAAAACCCUAACUUUGUAAACCAAAGAGUCAGAUUUAGAAGGAAACUUCAAGGCAGUGGAAAUAUAUAUCUUUUUUUAAAGUUGUCUUGUAGCCUUCUAUUUAAUAGAGCUUCUUUGGCUCUUAGACUAAAAUGUUUAACAUUUACUUAUUCACCAAACUAAUUAUUUAGGUGUAGUGUGUGUUAUGCAUAUGCUGUACUAAACCCAGGGCUGGAAUGAUAAACCUGACAACAUAUGUGUAUGUACAGUAUUUCUCCAUUCCCUCAACAAAUAAUCAUGGUGUAUCUGCUAUAUGUAAGGCAUAAUAUCAGGAAUUUCUGAUGCAAGGAUAAACAAAAUAGACACAGUCUCUGCACUACUGACAGUCUAGAAAGGAAGACAGAUUAAUCAGAUAAUCAUGCAAAUAAAUAUAAAAUUAUCACUAUGAAAAUGCUAGGAAGGAGAGGUGAACAGUGAGUGCUCACCUUUCAGAGCUCAGGGAAUUUGACCUAGUCUUUGGAGGGAGAUCAUGCAGGAGCUAGAAAACUUCCCCAAGGAACUGACUUUGGAUCUGAGAGUUAGAUGAUUAUUGGAAAUUAUGUAGUGAAGAGGAUGUGUGAAGAUUCUAGGAAGCAAAAAUAACAUGUAGAUCUUAUACAGUAUGAAGUGUGAAUUAUUUAUAAAGAAAGGAAGCAGUAUGGUUGGAAAUGUCAACCUAAGGAAAGAAAAUGAGGCAGAAUUAAUAUAGAGACUUUAUUUGGGUCAAGGUUGAGGACUGCAGCCUGGGAAACAUUGGGAAGUGCUCCAUUUGGCCUUGUUACAAGCAGGUGUUUUUUUGUUUGUUUGUUUUGUUUUUCUGAGACACAGUCUUACCCUGUUGCCCAGGCUGGAGUGCAGUGGCACAGUCUUGGCUCACUGCAACCUUCACCUCCCUGGUUCACGCGAUUCUCAUGCCUCAGGCUCCCAAGUAGCUGGGACUACAGGCAUGCACCACCACGCCUGGCUGAUUUUUGUAUUUUUGGUACAGACAGGGUUUCACCAUGUUGGCCAGGCUGGUCUCAAACUCCUGGCCCCAAGUGAUCCACCUGCUUCAGCCUCCCAAAGUGCUGGGAUUACAGGCAUGAGCCACCAUGCCCAGCCACAAGCAGAUAAGGCAAAAAGGGACAAGGGACUUUGUCUAAGACCACAAAAGGGGCUGAUACAAAUUUAUGUUUGACAUGAAUUCUUACUGGUUUACAAAAGUAACAUUGAUUACUAAUUGGCUAUAUGUUGUUGAACUAUAGUUUGUUAAGGUGUCUAGUGUAUGGUAUGUUUUGGCUACUUGGUGUCAGUUAGUCUACAGCCCACAUAGCAAGUGGCUUCAAGAGUUAGGUAUUUAGCUCAAGCGGGGAGCAAGACAUGACUGCUGUCACAUUUUUGUUUGUUUAUUUUUUAUUUUUGUAGAAAAGGUCUCGCUUUGUUGCCCAGGCUGGAUUCAGACUCCUAGGCUCAAGAGAUCCUCCUGCCUCAGCCUGCUGAGUAGCCAGAACUAUAGGCAUGCCAUGUCACAUUUUAAUGCUUCUCUGGGCCUGGUAAUUUAAAGGGACUUGAAUUUCUCAGAUUAAAAAUUUGUUUUCUUUCUCAGAACACAGAGAACAAGGGAAAGCAUCAUGCAAGAUGAGACAAGGGAAAGCAUCAUGCAAGAUGAGGCAAGAGAACUAUGGAAGAGGCCAGACCUAUCAGGGCCUUUUAAAAGAUUAAGGAUUUAAGUCUUUCAAGAGCAAUGGGAGGAUGUUGGAAGAUUUUAAGCAGUGUGUGUGUGUGUGUGUGUGUGUGUGUGCACGCGUGUGUGUGUGUUGUAGGGUGGCAGGGCAGGUAUGACAGGAUCAGAUUGUUCUUUCCAAAUAAUUGGUAUAGAAGGGACUAGAGGGGAAAAUGUGGAUGAGGGAGACCACUUUCAAGGCUAUUGAGUAACCCUGGUACAAGAUAGCUUGGAUUAGGGAGGAGGCCAGGGAAAUAUAGAAAGGUAUAAGCCUGAAACCCACUCUCACUACUUCCCCAUCCUCAAUUAUUUAAUUCCUUUUCAGAACAAGUUAUGUUAUAUGCCUGCAACCCAAAGGAUCUAAACUACAUCAUUUGGAAGAUUUUUAUUAUUCUCCAGCUUCCAGUUAGAAAUCUAAAAAAAAAAAAAAGGAAUGUAUUGCUUCAGCUGGUUCUCUCCCACUUUGCAUCAGAGAAUUUAGAUGAGCUGUCUUCCUCCAGUAGCUGGUUACUUAACCAGAAGCACAGUAAGAAAAAGAGAAAAGACAGGACAAGACUGAAAUCUUCAUCCUUGACUUUCAUGAGUACAUCAGCCCGAACAAGGCCACUUCAGAGUUUCCACAAACGAAAACUGUACAGAUUGAGCCCUACUUUUUAUUGGACUCCACAGACUUUGCCUUCAAAAGAAACAGCAUUUUUAAACACUACACAAAUGCCUUGCCUGCAAUCAGCUUCAACUUGGAGUAGCUAUGAACACAAUUCGGAGUCUUACCUAUUAAGAGAACAUGUAUCAGAGUUAGAUUCCUCUUUCCAUUCUGUUCUAUCAUUGCCAUCAGAUGUGCCUCUUCAUUUUCACUUUGAAACACUGUUAAAAAAGACUGAAAUAAAAGGCAAUCUUGCUGAAAAUAAAUUUGUAGAUGAAUAUAUCAUAUCUCCAUCACCUGUACAUAGUACUCUGAAUCAAUGGAGAAAUGGAUAUUCACCUAUAUGUAAGCCUCAAAUAAGGUCAGAAUCUUCUGCACAACUGUUACAGGGAAGAAAGAAAAGACAUUUGAGUGAAACAGCAUUAGGAGAAAGAACUAAACUUGAAGAAUCUGAUUUUCAACACACAGAAUCAGGAUCCCAUAGCAAUUUUACUGCUGUUUCCAAUGUCAACGUUUUAUCAAGAAUCCAGAAUUCAUCACGAAAUACUGCACGACGGAGAUUGAGAAGUGAGAGCUCUUAUGACAUAGAUAACAUUGUGAUUCCCAUGUCAUUAGUAGCCCCAGCUAAAUUAGAGAAACUCCAAUAUAAGGAAAUACUUACUCCAAGCUGGAGGAUGGUUGUUCUUCAGCCUUUGGAUGAAUAUAAUUUAGGCAAAGAAGAGAUAGAAGAUCUUUCUGAUGAAGUCUUCUCCCUAAGGCACAAAAAAUAUGAAGAGAGAGAGCAAGCCAGGUGGUCACUAUGGGAGCAAAGCAAGUGGCACAGAAGAAACAGCAGAGCUUACAGUAAAAAUGUUGAAGGACAGGACUUGCUUUUGAAAGAAUACCCUAAUAACUUCAGUAGCAGUCAGCAAUGUGCUGCUGCAAGUCCUCCUGGGCUUCCUUCAGAGAACCAGGAUCUGUGUGCAUAUGGCUUACCUUCUUUAAAUCAAAGUCAAGAAACCAAGUCUUUGUGGUGGGAACGACGGGCUUUUCCACUGAAGGGUGAAGACAUGGCAGCCUUAUUAUGUCAAGAUGAAAAAAAGGAUCAGGUUGAAAGGUCAAGCACAGCUUUCCAUGGUGAAAUCUUCGGUACCAGUGUACCAGAGAAUGGCCACCAUCCAAAAAAGCAGUCAGAUGGAAUGGAAGAAUACAAAACCUUUGGUCUAGGACUUACUAAUGUUAAAAAAAAUAGGUGACAGGGAACAGGUUAAGAAAACUAUGUAAAUGUAGGAAAGAUGGGAGGAAAUAAAGCCCUGUUCUGGAUCCCCCAUCCCCUCCAGAAUAAGAGCAUGUUCUGCAUGUAUUAAUCUUUUAUGCUGUUUAUGAAACAGGCAAGAUAAGUCUGUUUUUCCUUCUGGAACCAUAAGGGUAACCAGAUUUUCAUCUACAGACAAGUGGUAGUCAUUUGUGUUUAUCAUGCAACUUACUUACAAACACCAAGAUAUUAAUUGCUGCAACUUGAUGUCAAAUCACAUUACUGGGUAAUUUUUAAGACUAUGUACCCACACCAUACAUACAUACAUAUAUAUAUACACAUACAUACAAACCUGUGUGCCAAGUGACAGCUAUUUUUUUAUAUACAUGGUAAUUCAUUAAAAUUGCCUUAGUAAUAUAUUAGAAUAUACAAAUAUGUGUGUAUAAAAUAAACAUACACACACACACACACCCCUAUGUAGUUUUUAAAACACUGGCAAUGACCCACUCCCCUUGGAAAUGCAUGUAUGAACUACCCUAUGAAAUGUAAGCUGCAGAAUAGAUAAAACACAGGUUUCCACUAAUAAAAGACAUCUGAACGUCCUGAAUAUAGAGACAGAAGUUUUUUGUUGUUGUUGUUGUUGUUUUAACAUGUUUAACCAACAGAAGUUAUUUACAGAAAUUCAUAUAUCCAGGCAACACAAAACUCCUUUAUUCAAAAUCACUGCUAUCUUUGGGACUAAACACAGGCUACUUUCUGUUUACUCCUAACAAAAUAAAGCAAGCAAAUUUGAGUCAAAUAUUGGUGCACUUUAAUACUAUCACAUCUUUGAAAACUCAAUUUGAGUUUUACCAAUUAAUGUGUCUCAUGAAGAGAAGACACCAGUUUUAAAAUGAGCCACAAACAGUAAAGCCCUAUCAGUAUAAAAUUUGAAAAAAAAAAAAAAGAUGAUUGUAUUUCUAGAUUAGCAAGAAAUUAGUUAAUUCUGGCUGAUUUCUAUUUCUAGCUAAUUUGGUCAUUCUUUGCCAUAGCUUACUCUAUUCAAAUAAACAUAUAUUCUUGCUUGCAUCCUAGAUUGGAAAUUAAAAUUUUUCAAAGAACAAAGCUUCAAUAUUGGAUACUGAAGAGUAUACAUGAAAGAAAAUUCCUUUUGAAGCUAUUAAACCAUUUUUUUCCUAUGUGAAAGUUGAGGACAAUUUAUAUAACUCACUUUUUGUCAUGUAAAAAAGGUUACUCAAGUUGUACUACCCACAUAACUGAAAAUAUUGGCCAUUUGGCCUUAUCUGUGAGAUUUGACACUAAGUUUUUGUUAGAGAUUGGAAAUUAUACUAGUCCUUUUAAGGGGUAAAAAAUUCAAUUCAAUACUGACAAACUUUUGCUUGUAGUUUUACUGUACAUUUAUUUUUAAAGAAAAAGAAAACAAAAGCCAGACAAACCCAAGUUGUCCAGGCAAAUAAACUCAAAUCUUUGUCACGUCUGAUAUUAUAAUCUUCUAUGUAAGUUUUUUAAUUAAAGUUAUUUCUAUAUGC